CCUCAAGCUAUCCUUUGUUUUUGCCUCCCAGAGUUCUGGGAUUACAGGCAUGAGCCACUGUGCCCGGCCUCUGCCUAGUUUUAACAGUUGCUAAGAGGAGGAUGUUGAAGUAGAUGUCUUCUUGGUGGGUUAAUCCUUUUGUCAUUAAGCAGUUGUUAUGGUCACUUCCUUUUCACCCCAUUGGUGAAGGAGGGGUCCCUGCCCUAAAGUGUAGGAGAUGGCCGAACAUGACACCUGGCGUGGAUGGAUGAGAUUGACAGCAGUGUUUUAGUCGCAUAUACCCACAGCUCGGAGGAGGACACUGCAUGCCACACAGGGUCAGAUGGGCACCGCACUCUGUAGUGGAGUGAGGGCUGCGGGCUGAGGAAGCAGGCGGGCUUGGUAGUAACAAGAGCACACGAUGACCAAUGGUUCCCGAGGGGGAAUGCAAUUGGCUUGUUUGAAUAAAUUCAUGGGCUGGCAGACAGGUGAAGCGAAACUUCUUAGGCUGAGGUGCAACUGUUCUGGCUGAUAAAAGAACUAGCCAGGUGGGGAGCCUUUCCUGUUGGGUGGCGGGGUAGGGGGUGUCUGGUAGAAACAGGAAAACCCACGGCUAGGCCUUUGGGGCCCUGUGAGGCUCAAAGAUGUCAAGGCAGCAUAGGAAAUUUUAGAUCUUAAAAUUCAGCGAAGACCCUCUCCAGCUCUGGUUUUCUGCCUCCUGCUAAGCCAAUUUAUACAUUCCAAGAAAAUCUUCCAUUUCAUCCAGGUGAAACGGAACCUACUGGAAUGAAGCUGGCCUCCCAUGGAAUGAAGCUGGCCUCCCGUCUCCUUGAUUUGAAGCAGCUUCUCCACGUUGGUUAUUAUGCCAUUUUUCUAAAUCUAACAUUUUAAAAUUUGUGCCUUUUCUUUCUCUUUUGCUUGACUUCUCAGAGGUUUUUUUAACGGUCUUUUCAAAGAAGUGGUUUUGGGUUUUAUUUAUCAAGUCUACUUUUAUUAUGGCUGUUUUAAAAUUAAAUACAUUUAUUUCUUGUUUCCCUUAAAAAAGCUUCUUGUAUGUUUACUUAGUUUAUAUAAUUUUAUAUGUCUUCUGUUGAAGCAUAUUAACAAACACUUCCAGCUAUAACGUUUCCCCUGAGAACUGCUUUGGACACAUCCAGAGAUUUUGAUAGGUCACACACUUAUUGUAGUUUGUUUCUGAAAAGUUUUUCAUUUUAGUUUUUAUUUUCUCUUUUACUCAAAUUAUCAUGAGCUUUCUCCUUUUAUCCUGUUUCUGACAAAUUAAUCUGAGGAUAUAAAUUUCUCCCUAAAUGUCAAUUUUGUUGAGUUUCAUAAUUUUAAUAUGUAAUACCCUAUUGCUAUUGAGUUCCAGGCAUUUUAUAAUUUUCAUUGUGAAAACUAACUUUGUUUCCAAAACACACUUUUUCUUCUUUUUUGAGACAGAGUUUCACUCUGUCACUCAGGCUGGAGUGCAGUAGCACAAUCUCAUCUCACUGCAACCUCUGCCUCCUAAGUUUAGGUGAUUUUGUUGCCUCAGCCUCCCUAGUAGCCGGGUUUACAGGCUCUUGCCACUAUGCCUGGCUAAUUUUUUGUAUUUUUAGUAGAGACAGGGUUUCGUCAUGUUGCCCAGGCUGGUCUCGAUCUCCUGACCUGGGGUGAUCCACCCGCUUCAGCCUCUCAAAGUGCUGCGAUUACAGGCAUGAGCCACCGUGCCCGGCCCCAAAAUGCACUUUUAACAUGGUCUUUGUUAUUGCAUGUUUCUAAUUUUGUUGCACCCUGGUGAGAGAAUGUGAUUUGUGUAACAGCAAUUCUUGGGAAAGGGGCUGAGGCUUCCUGCUCCUUUAGCACAGCUAAAUUUUCCCAAACGCCAUCCAUGAGCUUGGAAAGAGCAUUGUACUCUGUUGGGAUGGGCUCAAAUCUCUCUGUAAAAAUGAGUGUUCUUCUGUUGUUGUUGUUCUGUUUUUUGUUUGUUUUGUUUUGUUUGUUUUUUGUCUCAGUCGUUUUGUUUGCUCAGAUCUUUUGAUGAUCCGGAUGAUCUUUUAAUUUAUGCAGGAUGUUUCUCUGCUUGUGCAGGCUGGUGGGAUUGGGGACUGGAGAGAGGAUAAGUGUCUGCUUGCCCAGGACUGGCAAACUGUCACUUGCCCUGGUUGUGCCUUGCCAGGAGCUCCCGUGCCUGUCUCUGAGAGUGUCAUGAGCGCAGCGGUGGUAGUUGUGUGGUGGAUGCAUUUCCCCUGGGUUGGGGGGUGGGUGGCUGGUCCUAGCUCUGUUUGUUGUUGCCGAUGAGACACAGCACACUUCUGCUUCCUGAUGGAUCUUGUCGGUCAUUUGACUUCUUCCUGGUCUGGGUUCCUGAGCUGGCCCUCCACAGGCCAAGCAGGAAUGGAGCUGGCUGCUACAAGAGUUCCUUCACUAGAGGGCAUCUCUCCUCUCUCCUCCCACACAUGGGAGCACAAGGGUGGGCUUUCCUCCGCCCACUGUGAUCCGCAGCCCGGCUUUCCCCUCCUCACCCUCUGCUCUCAGACAGACUUGCUUUUCGCUGGUGUCUGUGAGAGGUGAUUCUUCAUGGUGCCAAGAAUAUGGAUUUUUUUGAGAGCAGGCUCUCUCACAGAUAUUUGCACACCCAUGUUCAAAGCAGCGUGAUUCACAAGAGUCAAAAGGUAGAAGCAUUCUGAGGGUCUAUGGGUGAGUGGAUGGGCAAGCGAAAUGUGGUUAUGCAUACAGUAGACUGUUACUGAACCUUUACCAGGAAGGAGAUUCUUUUUUUUCUUUCUUUUUGUGGAAAAUGCGGUCUCGCUAUAUUGCCCAGGCAGGUCUCGAACUCCUGGGUUCAAGCUAUCUUCCUACCUCUGUCUCCCUAACAGCUAGGAUAAUAGGCGUGAGCCUAUAAUAUCACCCAGCCAGGAGGGAAAUUCUGAGAGGUGUGCCAACACGCAUGAACCUUGAGGACAUUGUGCUAGAUGGAAUAAGCCAGCCACAAAAGGACAAAUACAUUGCGAUUUCACUUACAUGAGGGGCCCAGAAUGGGCAAAUUCAAAUACAGAAAGAGCAAUGGUUAACAAAAGGAGGGAGUUGGUGUUCAGUGGGUAUGGUUUCCUUUUGGGAAGAUGAAGAAGUUCUGGAGAUGGACGGUGGUAGGGGAUAUGCGACAAUGUGAGUGCACUUAAUGCCGGUUAUAACAAGGGGAGUGCGUGUGCACACGGCUCUGGGAGUUCUCGUGCAGCACUCAGAGCUCAGCGUGGGCGAGGGCGUCACCCCUCUGGGGGCGUCCAUGGGGCCUUGGAGAAGGGAGGCUCCAGGGCACCAGAGCAGUCUACCCGGAGAGGCCGGGCCGAGAGCUUGUUCACCCCCAGCCCUCUUAGGGAACUUUCACAUGCUUCUCCCACUAGGCCUAGGCACCCCUCCCUACCCUCCCUACCCUCCUGGUUCCCUGACCCUCAGUGACUGUGUCCUUCAAGACUGAACUCCAGAGUCCCCACCCGAGGACCCGCAGUGCCCAGCCCCCGCGAGCUCGCGGGGUGUAUGCCCACCCCGAGGCUCCACCGUGCCUGUGUGCUGGGAAGCCUGGCUCCAUGGGACCCUCGGGCUCUGGGUGCGCCGUCGCUGCAGCUGCCAGCAGCUCCUGAGGAAGUGGCUCGAGGCCCUGGGGCGGGCCAGGCAUGCGGUGGGCCCGCUGCCCUCACACCGGCCCCGGCCACACACAGGAGGCGCAAUCAGCAGAGACGUUGGACAGGGUUGGACACUGGCUGUCUCUUUCGGGCCUCGGUUUUCACGUCUGAAAUAAAAGCGAGCAUCCUGGCCCUGGUGCUGUGCCUCUGCCGCGGUAGAGGUUUCCACCCCUAUGAGCCCAGUGCACCUUCCAGGCUCGAGGGAGAGGGAGUGUGCGUGCGUGUGAACGCGUCACACUCUUGUGUGAAUGCGUCAUACUCUUGUGAAAGACUGUGCGUGUGCACACGCGUGUACGUGCAUGUGAACGCGUCAGGGUGCCUGAGGAUGCACACAUGCACGUGUGAGUGUGCGCGAGUGCGUGCUCAGAGGACAGCUCUCAGCAGGCUGGGGACCUCCUUCCUCUCACCCCUGAGGGUUUUGGGGGACCAGCCCCCGUCUCCGGGUGCUGUGGGAUGUCCUGGGGCGAGCUCGCACCGCUGUGCUCGGGCUCCGGCUUUGUGGGGACCCGGCCUUCCCGGCCCGCACCACGGGGAGUUCCACGCAGCACCCACGAGGUGGCGCCGCAGACUCGCUACCGCGGAGCGCGGCGGCUCCUGGCUCCCAGCAGCCUUGCCUACAGCUGUGGCCAGGGCGAUCCCUCUCAGGCCCAGGCCGCUGCUGCCAGGAAGAGCAGGAACAACAGCCAGUCACGCCUGGUGAUGCCUCUGAAGUGCUUAUGCUCCCAGGCAUGGGCUGACCGCAACGUGCAUUCUCUCCUUUUAUGCCCCUACUAUUUGGAACGCUGUAUUUUUUCAUUUUUAUUUUUAUUUUUUGUUGUAAAUCUGCCACUUAAAAAUACCCAGGGUGGAGCUAAAAGUACAGACACUGCUCAACUUACCCCUGGCUGCGGCCCGAUAAGGCCGCUGCGAGUGGAAAAUGACUGAGUCCACCUGACUACCGAAUAGCACAGCGUGGGGGGGCCCACCUUGGCCUGCUGAGAACACUGCCCUGAGCCUGCGGUGGGCAGAAGCAUCAACACGAAGCCUGUUUUGUAGUCAAGUGUCGGAUACCUCAUGUAAUCAUUGACUGCUGUACUGAAAGCGAAAAACUGGCCGUGUGGGACUCACACGAGGGUUUCUGCUGACUGUGGAUGGCUUUUGCAUCACUAUAAAGUUGAAAACUGUUAAGUGGAACUGCGGUAAGUCGGGGCUGUGUGCACUAGAGACCUGAGUUCUGCCGCUCCAUAGCUGUGUGACUUUGGACACAUAUUUGAGCCUGAGUGUCUUCCACACAAAAUGGAUUUCUUAGCAUAACCUACACAUGUGUACGUGCCUGUGAGCGUGCACGUGUGUGUUUGCAUGAACACAUCUGUGUAUGCACGAGUGUGUGCACAUUUGUAUGUGUCUGUGUAAGUCCGUAUGUACAUUUGUGUGCAUGUCUGUGUGUGCAUAUGUUUGUAUGUGUGUGUGCUAUGCAUGUGUGUGUUAAGGCCCUGGGGUGGAGCUGAGGAGUUGAGGGGAGAUGCUGGGAGGGCAGCCAGCACCAGGCGUUUGUUGGCCAGGAGAGAAGCUGCCAUCCAGGUGCACUCUGGAGCUCGUGCUUCAGUGGCACAAGGCUUUGGGAGUGAGGAAGCUGGGGGCUGGGGCAGGGCAGUCCUGCACCUCAGGGGAGGUGCAGAGUGAGGCCAGGAGGAUGGAAAGAGUGCCAGAGAAUGGGGGAAAUCUGAGGCAUCAGGAAAGGAAGACACAGGCCAUGGAGAGGGCAGCUGGGCCCUGGGUGAGGCCGGCCCUCAGGAAGGAGGUGCCACAGGCAGGGGAGUGCCCAGAUGGAGAGCCCAGGGGUAUGGACCCACGGGUGUAUGACAGUGGGGGUACUCCUGAAACAGAGCAGUGUUAUCCAACAAGCAGGGUUGGGACAGCUAGUUAUUUCAUUUAAAAAAACAGGUCAAUGUCAGUCCUCAUACUGUGCUUUAAAAUAAGCUCCAGAUGGACUCAUCUUUUACAUGUAAAGAAUAAAAGGCAAAAAGAAAAUAAAGAAAAGUCUUGUAAGCAGGUAGUUAAUUGGAGGCAAUCCCAGGAUGCAGGAGAGAGGUGAAAUACUUUUAGACCUAAAAUUUGAAAAAUAUAGUAAAAAUGAUUCCCAUAUGUGCCUCUUUCAGCUUGCUCUAAUGUCAGCAUCAUAAAUAACCACAGCAUAAGUAUCACAACCAUGAAAUGAACAUAGAUAUAAUGUUAUUUGUUAACUCAUUUAAAAUACCAUAUGGAUUUCACUGAUUUUUCCCGUUGAUGACUUUUUUUAUGUUACAAGAUAAAAUUCAGGUUUCUGUAUUUUAUUUGGUUAUCCUGUCCUUAAUAUCUUUAAAUCUGUGAUAGUUUUUCACUUU